AACCCGCGAGCUUACACCGGCUUCUCUCUGUCCUCAGCCCGCGCGCCGCCAUCGCCGUCAUGCUGGGCGCCGCUCUCCGCCGCUGCGCUGUGGCCGCAACCACCCGGGCCGACCCUCGAGGCCUCCUGCACUCCGCCCGGACCCCCGGCCCCGCCGUGGCUAUCCAGUCAGUUCGCUGCUAUUCCCAUGGGUCACAGGAGACAGAUGAGGAGUUUGAUGCUCGCUGGGUAACAUACUUCAACAAGCCAGAUAUAGAUGCCUGGGAAUUGCGUAAAGGGAUAAACACACUUGUUACCUAUGAUAUGGUUCCAGAGCCCAAAAUCAUUGAUGCUGCUUUGCGGGCAUGCAGACGGUUAAAUGAUUUUGCUAGUACAGUUCGUAUCCUAGAGGUUGUUAAGGACAAAGCAGGACCUCAUAAGGAAAUCUACCCCUAUGUCAUCCAGGAACUUAGACCAACUUUAAAUGAACUGGGAAUCUCCACUCCGGAGGAACUGGGCCUUGACAAAGUGUAAACCGCAUGGAUGGGCUUCCCCAAGGAUUUAUUGACAUUGCUACUUGAGUGUGAACAGUUACCUGGAAAUACUGAUGAUAACAUAUUACCUUAUUUGAACAAGUUUUCCUUUAUUGAGUACCAAGCCAUGUAAUGGUAACUUGGACUUUAAUAAAAGGGAAAUGAGUUUGAACUGAAAUUAGGUAUUUGUUUCAUGUGUUUGCAUUAAUAAGCAGAAAAUUAAGUGCUGUAUUGGUUUCAUGGUUUUGCUGCCCUCUUACAUGCUGAGAGAACUGUGUUAAUUCUCUGGAAACCAUCUGACAUGAAAAUCAGCUUCAUUAAUAUGUUUGGGUGCCCUAGCUUGUAAAUUAGCUGAAGGCUAGAAGUCAUUUAUAUAGAAUUUUCUUGUUGACACCCUAGGCUUAGGGGACUGGUUGUCUGUGGGGAUAGAUCAAAUUGUGUACCUUUCCAAAACAGGUUUUAAUGAUGUUUAAAAGUGGUCACUGAGAUAGUCUUGAGGAUGUGCUAUGCAGUAGCCAAGCCCUCUUACGGUGUGUUCCUCUCUUAGUGCCCCUUUCCUUUCCUACCUGUUCUUCCCUUGCAGUGGUGUAUUAGCCUUGGACAUUAAAACAUUUGCUUUGUAAAUUUGGAGGCAUUCUGAUUAAACAGCUGAGUAAAACAAA